AGUGUGAAAGGAGUCAGGGCUAGAGGCAGCAGAGGGAACAGCAAAGAAGAGCCGGUGAGUAAGUGGUUAUCUGUCUGGUCUAUGUUUGUCUGGGUGGCUCUGGAACAGAAAAGGAAGCCUAGAUAUACCCAUUCUAUCAGCCAGAGUGGGCUUUUGUUACAACCAGAUACAAAUUCUCAGCUUGAGGCCAGAUUCCAGUAUCAUUACUAUUUAUUAGAAGGAAAUCUUUAAAAUUAUCUUAGUCCAAGGGAGUGAACUGCUCAGCGCAGAAGCCAGAGAUACAAACCAUUGUCUGUCCUGAUGUCAAGACAAUGGUUUUGUGUGGCCACCCUGAGCACAAAGCUGGAGCUGCUAGUCUUCCUCCUUCUCUCUGAGCCAUUGUCUCCAGAGAGGCGCUCGGUAGCUCUGGUCAGAAGCAGCGUCGGCCUCUCUUGUGGGCCGAUUUCCUGGAUGGGGCCACGGGAGGAAGGUGGAGGGGACAGAGCCACAGGAGACUGGCAUGGCUGUGCUCCUGGUUUUAUCCUUUUACUUAGCAGAGUCAGGUGUGGUGAGAUGUAGGGUAAGACAGAACCUGGCGGGGGUGGGUGCAGAGAGUUGCGGGGAGAACUCUUCACUCAUUAAGAAGACAAGGUUGUCAGUUGAGAACAAAACUGAAAUCCAGGGAGAAAGAGAACCAACCUUUUGCAUUUAGAUUUCUGUUGCCCCCAUUCCCUCAACUUCCCCUUCAGGUCCCUCAUCCCUUCAACCUCCAAAACAUUUGUGCUCUUUGACCCUGGCACCUUCUAAUGACAGUUUUGUGGAGGGGGUGUGGACAAGAAUUCCUUGGCUUGGAGGAGGAGGUGGACGCACUGGCUUUUCUCAGCUGAUGCUAUCUCUCUGUGUGUGUACUCAUGAAUGCCCACGUGAUUUAAAAAAAAAAAAAAAGAGGGAGACUGUCACCAAAAAGGAAGUGCUUACUUUACUCUCCUCCCGCCCCCAGCUAGGAGCCCUUUUGUUCCCUUGCCUCUUUCUUGGGAGGAAAGAGAUUCGAUGACAUAGUGAUGCUAGGUUGAACCUAGGGAGGAACUCGGGGCUCUGGAGAGCCUAUUAGGUGGGAACAGGGUGCUCCCUGUGCCAGUUUAGAAAGCAGAUUCGAGCGAUAAGGUAAACCCAACCCCCUUGUGGCUUUCAGCUGUGGUGCUUCCUCUGGCUGGGCUGCCCAUGGGCAAACAGAAACCAGGCACAAUAGGGGGAAGGUGCCAGCCACUAGACCCAGCAGGGCGAGAGCAGAAGCAGCCAAGUUUCUGGGCAUUUGAGGCCAAGAAAGAAGGGGAAGUAGAGUAUAGGAGAGGAACGGGGAUACUUGUUGUGUUCUGCCUCAUAUUGAGAGUCAGCCACAAAUGUGACUAGCCAACCUCCAUCCCUACACUCCCAGGAGAAGUAUACUGGGAUUGUUAUUUCCAGGCAGGGCAGGGGGGCUUCAUGGGGGAUGCAAACUGUGCAGUUGCCCCACAUGCUUGGUUUAAUGCUCUGCUAUUGCUGUCUUGAAAUCCUUAAGUUUUGCACAAGGGGCCCGCAAAUUGUGCAGCUGGUCUUAUUUCCUGGCCCAGCCAGAAGUUGCAGGUGCAGAAUAGUUGCUCAUAUACUCCAACAGGUGUAGGCAGGCUCACCUGUUACUCAGGUGUCACUUAUGGAGGCCGGCUUCUGUCCCGGCUGGCACCUGUGCUGCAUCCCUUUCCCUUUCCUCCUCUCUGUUCCCCUCCCAGAGUACUCUAUUCCUCCUUGUCACAGCCUCCAUGCCCAGUCUUUCUUCACGGCUGCUGCGUGGCAGGACAGGGGUGGGAACAGCAGUGUCCCUUGUCUGACUGCCUCCCUGCCUUCCUUCUCAGGCCCUCUCUUUUCCUUAUCUGGGCUAUAGCCAGCAGGUUCUCUAGGCUAGGUCUAGGCCUAGGAGCACCUCUUCCGUUCCUCUGAGAUUGUCUUCCCUCCCCUCUGUAAGCCCCGGUUAUCAGUGGAUGCUCUCUGGCACCUGCUUCUUGUGAUGUCUGCUUAGCAACAGGUUGUUUACCUGUGAUUUCCAUAGGAUCCAGGUCUGGAUGAGUGCUGGGUGGGGAAGGGGAGGUGCAGGGAAGGAAGAAUCCUAAGCCUGCUGUCCUUGGUGGUACUUCCUCUACCCUGUCCUCCUCCAUGCCAGCUUCUCCUGCUCUGGACCAAAUGGCCCCACAGAAGACCUCCCUUUCCUCCUCCUCCCCCAAGCGUCAGCUAGAGGUUGGCCAAUCCAGGAAGGAAAAGGAAAGCAGGAGGGAGGAACAGGUCCUCUGUGUCUCCAGCCUCCUCCCCAACUCUUCUUCCUUCUCCAACUCUUCUCUCCCAGCCUCCUUAAGCUGCUGGAUGACCUUUUCCAGUGUUUCCUACCAGGCCAGUGCUGUUAGUAAUGAUACUUUCAAACUGUGCAGAGGAGUCUUAAUGCAUGUGAUUUAAAAAUAAUGAGCCUGGCCAACACGGCGAGACCGUGUCUCUACUAAAAAUACAACAAAUUAGCCAAGCGUGGUGGCCCGUGCCUGACGUUCCAGCUACUGGGGAGGCUGAGGUGGGAGAAUUGCUUGAGCUCAGGGAGCGGAGCCUGCGGUGAGCCAAAAUCGCACUACUGAACUCCAGCCUGGGAUACAGAACAAGAACGUGUCUCAAAAAAAACAAAAACAAAAACAACCAAAAAAAAACCAACAACAACAACAAAAACAACAAAAAACCCAAAAAAACGAAAACAAUGGAUUGUCCAGAUUAAUUCUGAGUGAACUUUGGAGUAUAUCAUUUCUGAUUUUUAACUUUUUGUUGUUGACAGCAGAUUUUCCUUUCUUUUUAGCUUAGUUUAGGUCUAUGAGGGAACUUGUAUUUACUGAAGACACUGAGCUCAUCAGCUGGUGGAAGGAUACACUGGCUUAGAAUUGCAUUUCAUAGAAUUCAAAACUAUUAGAACUGGAAGGUGGCUUAGAGAACAUCUAGCCUAGUGCUGUCCAAUAGAAUGUUCUACAAUGAUGGAAUGUCCUGUGACUAUUCUGUCCCGUAUGGUAACCACUAGCUACUGUGGCUCUUGAGACACAGUGAAAUGUGGCUAGUGUAACUAGGAACUGAAAUUUUAAUUUUAUUUAAUUUUAAUUAUUCAAGAUAGAAUACGGCUAGUGGCUAUCAACUUGGUGCAAAUUUAGGAUAGUGCUAUUUAUUGUAUUCCCUUAUUUUAUUAAUGAUUAUAACAUUAGCCACUACUAAACAACUCAAUGUGCCAGGCAUUCUUCUAGAGGUUUUAAAUAUUUAGUCCUCCCAGCAACUCCAGUAUCGUUACAUGUUGCAGGUGGGGAAACUGAGACCCAGAAAGGGACAGUGACUCAGUAGUGGUCAGUUACCAAGACUCCUGACUCUGAGACCACCGGCCUUACCCUUUUCCUUAAGGACAAUCCACACGCUGUCCAUUCCUUGCCAUCAUGUGCCAGCUUUUUUCACAACUCUCCAGUCCCUUUCCAGAUCUCCCUCUUCCUCUCGGGGGCGUCAGGGGAGCUCACAAAGGAUCGUCUCAGUCUGCAGCAAGUGCUCUCCUAGGCACAGUCAUUUUCUGGCUGGUUCCUUGGGUGGCCCUUGUUCCUAGGCUCCCUUUGGAUCCCCCACCAGCAGGCAGCAGUGCAGGGAUAUCGCUUUGCCCUCAGAGUCCUUGGCAAGCUCCCCAAGUACAGGGGAAGUUCCAGAUUCCUUGCUCCUGGCAAAAGGAGGUGUUCAUAAUUUCCCACAAUCCACCUGGCUCCAGCUUACCCUAUUACUCCCAGUCUGAGAGAGAACAUCAGCUGAGCCCUCCUUGGGGGCCGGAGGCAGAAUGGGUCUCCCUGGGCAGGUGAGGAGCAGCACUACAUUAGAGCCUGCUGUUGCCCCUCAACCCUUGCUGUGCUACCCUCCAGCCAGGAGGCUCCUGCUCUCCAGCUCUGGCUGGUUUACUGCUUUCCUCUUCCCAGGGCAAAGCUUCUGCUUUGUAGACUCUUAUCAGAGUCUGGCUGGCCAGUAGGGAGGGGAGGGACAGGAGGGGGCAUGAAGCAGAUGCACUGUGCACACUGAUCCCGGCGAGAGGGAUUUGAGGCUGAGCUCCUGUCUCCUUCAGCCGCUAUUCAGCAUCCCAACUGGAACAGCACGUGCCCCCUCCUCCAGGCAGUGGUGAGCCUGCUGGCCUGCCCUACAGCUGCUCCAUCAAACUCAAACAGUUAUUCAGUUCCCCUGUGUGUGAGGUGCUGGGCAGGGGCACAGCAAUAAAGGCCAGGCUGUGGACAGUGUUUGUGUGGCUGCCCUUCCAUGCCCCUACAUCCAGGCAGCUGUUGUCAGACUAAAGUUUGUGGGUAGCCCCCAGCCCACAUCACACACAGUCCCCAGACCUGUAGCCCACAGAUAUUACCAGUGAAAGAGUUUGUGGCUUUCAUUACUGUGUUCUUGGAGCAGACCUUGAAAAGCUGGCAUCUCCCCCUGAACCAUGAAGCUCUCUCCUGCUUUCCUAGGGGCAGGGAGCUCAGAUUGGGUGCAUCGCAGGAACAGAAAGAAGGGAGCCCAAGACUCAAAUUUUUCUGACCUCUCCUGUCACUAUAGCUGGGACAAUGCACCUCAGCUUCCCUGAUUCUAAAAUGGGCCUUCCUUGCCUCCCUCCCAGUGUAAGGACCAGAGAUUGCAUGCGUUUUAUUUUUCUCUUCAUUCCACAUGCCUUCAGAGCAUCAUAACCUUUCUUCCUCUGCUCUCUGGUCCAGUGGGAGAUUUGUGUUGUCUGCUCAACAAGGCAUCACUCAAUACCAUUGUUUUACUGUUAAAAUGAGAAAACUAAGAUACCAGACAGCUUGAUUCUCAAAUUGCUGGAUUGGGAACCAAGAAGGCACUGGUAGCUUUUGAGGAUGGGGAAGGAGAGAGAUCAGCCAGCUUCAUAACUCUCCAAACACCCACUUUGUAAAAUUCCUUUCGUUGGGUGGGGCAGGGUGGGGUCGCUGCUCUCCGUAGGACACCAGAAGCAGAUCUGCUGAGUUAGGGAUGCAGAGACAUGGUUUCAAUGACCUUCCAUAGACCCGGCGGCGGACAGCUGGGCUGCCUCAGCCACUGAAGGGCAGGGGUUUGAGAUUCAACUCAGAGCUGGAAGGCGGCGGGGCGGUGGGGGGGCAUAAUUAAUUAUUGCCCUGCCCUGUUACCCCUUGGGAUCCGUUCCACAUUGCUGGCUGUCAGGAGAAGGCAACUUGGAGGCGAGGGGGCUGGGGCCUUUUUUCUCUGCUUCUGUCUGGCUUAGCUACUGAGGAAAGGCUGAGAGGAGGAAAACCCAGAGCUGUAGGCAGCUGGUUCUCCUUUGAAUUCCCCCUCUCUUUAGAAGGGAACAAGAGCACACAGCACAAGGAGGAGCUCCAGGGAGCUGGAUUGCCCCAGUUCUCCAAUUUGGGUCAGGGUGAAGGAGAAAGUGUCUCCCAGCCUGCCCAUGGCAGCUUCUGGGUGGUAGAAUCGCAGUUCCCCACAAUUGGAAGACACUUCAGUGUUGAGACAGUUAAGGACUGGCUGUACCCGGGAAUGAUAUUCAAUAAUUCAUCAACCAGAAAGGAUGCUGGCCUGGAGUCUUGGAGGGCCCUGUGGUGCCAGGCAUUAACUCUUUUGUCUCUGGGUCAUGGAGAUGUGAGGAGGUCUCAGACCCUGGCCCAGAGAUGGGGCAGGGACACUCGAGGGACUUGGGGGAGCAGCUUUUCACCCACCAACAUGGAAGAGCUUCAGUAUUUGAAUCACUGGCAGAGUUAUGCUAUCUACUCUGGUUGUCUUCAUUUUUCAGCAGACAGAUGGAAUUCCCUAAAGUAAAACAACCAGUUUAAAGAUGAACCAAGCUAGGGUGGGAGGUCAGGAUGAAGUUCCCCUGUAUAGUAUCCAUGUUUUCUCUCAUGCACACACACGUGCGUGCACACACAUGAGCUUGAACCCGUUACCCUGACUGAAGUACACCUUGUCCUCCUGCCCUCAGUCUGCCAUCUUAGGCCUUCCUAUCUCCUCUCAUAGGAAUAAGGGACCACCCAGGCCCAGAGCAGGGGCUGGGAGACACUACAGUGAGAAAAUGGGGGAAGGACAGCACCUGAGCUGGAAGGGAAGAAACCUGGACCUGGCCCCCUGAUUUGUGAUUUCUCUCCCUUGUCCACGGAGCCAUCUCUUCUAUCUUCUGCCUGUGGUGGGAGCUGAGCUCACGUAGAAGGCCCCCAGCCUUCCAUAACUGCCCAUAACAGGUUUUGGGAUGGGGCUGGGGGUGCGGUGUGGCUGGGCAGAGUGAAGCAGGAAAGGGAGCAGCAUGAGUCUUGUCUCCUAGACAUGCAGCCGAGUAGCUUAGAACAUUUCAAUAAACUGGCUUGGGGCAGGGAGGUACCAUCUUCUUGACAGUUUGGAAAUAACUGUGGCAUCAAAGGGGGGAUGAGCAAGGGCAGAGAAGAAAGGUGAAAGCAAAUACAAGGCUGGGUGACAGCCACUGGCAGCUGGUUCCCAGCACCCAGAGAACUGGUAUUUUGAUCUUCAAGGAGCACAUGGAAGAGAGACAGUAGGGGUUGUUGUUUUUAGAGACAGGAGGGUCUUGCUCUGUUGUUUUUUAGAGACAGGGGUCUUACUCUGUUUUUUUUGUUUUUUUGAGACGGAAUCUCUGUCUGUUGCCCAGGCUGGAGUGCAGUGGCGCAAUCUCGGCUCACUGCAAGCUCCACCUCCUGGGUUCACGCCAUUCUCCUGCCUCAGCCUCCUGAGUAGCUGGGACUACAGGUGCCCGCCACCAGGCCCGGCUAAUUUUUUGUAUUUUUAGUAGAGACAGGGUUUCACUGUGUUAGCCAGGAUGGUCUUGAUCUCCUGACCUCGUGAUCUGCCCGCCUCUGCCUCCCAAAGUGCUGGGGUGACAGGUGUGAGCCACCGCCCCCGGCCUUUUUUGUUUGUUUGUUUUUGGUUUUUUUUAGAGAUGGGGGCCUUGCUCUGUUGUUUUUUAGUGACGAGGGUCUUGUGCCUCAGGUUGGGGUGCAGUGGUGUGAUCAUAGUUCACUGCAGUCUCGACCUCCUGGGCUCAAGUGAUCCUCCUGCCUCUGCCUCUGAGUAGCUGGGACUACAGACAUGUGCUACCAUGCCUGGCUAAGGCAGUGUUGUUUGGAGGGGUUCCUUCCCACCUGCAAAUACCUAGAAGUGCUGCCAGGGCCUGACCCUCUUUGACCUCUUCUUUAUGUGGCAGCAAUAGGUAGGAAAACAGAGGGCCUCUGAUGAGAAGUGGCUAGGAAAGUGUAUUUUCUCCUGGAAAUGGCAGGGGGAGCUUCAGGAAUCAGGUGCAUGAAGAUGGCUGGAAACAUAAACUGAGUUGGUUUUUAAUUGGGACAGGAUGCUGAAGCAGAUAAGCCUCCUUGAAAAUAAUGAUGAGAUCCAGAUGGGGAGGCACAGAGCAGGAGCCAACCUUCUCCCCACCUUCCCCUCCUCUGUGGCAGCAGAAAUCCUCUCUGGAGCAUGGACAGUCUCGGCUUGGAAUUUGCUAGCUGGGAGAAAGAAGGAAGUGGAAGGGAUGGGACCCCCUUUCCACUUGCCUUGCAUGCAAACCUCUCUCCACCUAAUGAGCUGUAAUGCUGGAAGCCAAGGCGUCCUCAGGAUGGGGAAGCUGGGCCAGGGCUAAUUCUUUGUCAGCAGAUUCUCAGGAGCUAUGGAAAUGAAGCAGCUUGGUGUACAGCAGAUAAUCAAGAGAGGCCCAGUGGGUGGAAGGAGUGGAGUAUUUCUCCAGUCGUUCAAUAUUGAUCACAGUGGGGUUCUGGGCAUCCAGCCUGGGAGUGUGUGUGCAUGUGUAAACAUACAUGCCUGCAAAAGAUCGUGAAACUUGGAUUAAUUUUGCCACUCUUGACAGUGUAGUGCCAGGUAUACUGCACGUGGAGGCUGACUCUCCAGGGGGAUGUUUGGAGAUGAAGCAAUGCAGAGUUAUCUCUAUGUGAGGUACUGUAGGGGUUGAGGAUGUCUCUUGAACUACAGGAAAGCUUUAAAUAGGUGCAGAGACAAAGGCCUGGAAAAAUAGAGAGGAUCUGCUUCUUUUCUUUGUAAUUUAUCGCUCUUGAGACUUCCAGAGUGCCUGCCCCUGGCACUCCCAGCCUGUGCCCCAUACACGAUCUUCUUAAGCCUGGGACUAAGUAUUUUUCAUUUUUUCGCUCCUUCAUCUGGCAUAUAUCUUAAUUUGUUUUUAAGUAGAAUGAUCAUAGCCAUUAUCUCUUCUGCAAAAAAUGGUCUAUAUCUUGCAAGUUUACAGCUAUUAUUUCAUAGAAUUAGUGUCUGUGCUGGUGAAGUGAGCACUAUUAUUUCAUGUAGUUAGAAGGUACCUCAUUUACACAUGAGAAAACUAAGGGCCCAAGAAAUAAAGUCAUAUUCCUAACUCAGGUUGGAUCUUGGACUGAAUGUUUGGUCCUGCCAUGUUUGUUUCCACUGAUGGCACUGCCAUCAGGGCCACCCUCAUUGUGGAUAAGUGACCACCUACUGGACUGCUCUGGAGUUUAGGGCUGUUUCUACCUCCACCGCACAAUCUCCUUUACCACUUGAGAUUUUCCCUUCUCUUGGGUGGAAUUUGAAAGGUCCAUUUGGGUAUGUAUUCAUGGAUUCAUAAUCAUUUGUCCUUGACAAAUGGAAGCCUUUUGACAUCCCAAAAGGAAGGAGAGAAGAAGGAGAAAACGGAUUACCUGUCCUUGUUUCCCUUUUUAAUGUUCUGCCUCUUGUAAGUUCUUCUUGAUGUCUAACUAAAAUGAAAAUUUGCCAUACUCUGCAGUUUAUUGGCAAAGGGAAAGAACUGCUGCUAGACAUUCUGUGUGCAGACUUAAUUCCUAGGAGUUCAGAGCUCUUGAUGAGCAGGGGAAGCCCCUGAGCCUUCCUUCGUUCCUACUCCCUUGUGCUAUCUUUACAGGGCAUAGGAGAAGUAAUUUAACUUGCAGCUUAAGCAAAGGCUGUGGGAGGCCCCUGAGCUCAGCUUGAAGUGAAAGGGGAUAUUUUUGCCUUCUAGAGGAAGAAAGCUCAUUUUCCCAAAGCGCCCCUACCCCCUCCUCCUUCUGUGCAGAUGAGCUUAAUUUUCUUCCCGUCCUACUGAAGGUGGAUCAAAGCCAAGCUAUGUAUUCAAGGGGGAGCUAGGCAGGGAAGCUGAGUGAGGGGGCGAGGGGGCAGAAGCAAAGCUUCUCUCAUGGAGAGGAAGUAAUUAAUUUUAAGAGAGAGCUAAGAUAGGGAAGCCCUCGGUGAUAGAAUGUCAAACUCCAAAUGCAGGUGGUUAAAAAUUAAGUCAGGGCUGGAGAGUUUCUAUUAUUCAUUCAUUCAACAAAUAUUUAUCGAGCACCUGUUAUGUAUGGGCAGGAACCUCAAGCCGGCAUCAGGAGAGGGCCCAAGAAACUGGAUUAGGGACAGGGAAAGGAUGUGAUCUGAAAACCGAGGCCUCCUGUCACCAGGAUAAAUCAUUUGCAAAAGUCCCACGAAAUAGCUGAAUAUAUUGACCUUCUGGAUUUAAGAUUAAGCUGUUUAAAUAUCAGCAGCGGUUGACCCCAGUUACAUCCUACCAACUUGUCUCAUUAUGGGUUAAAUAAUAAUGUUGUCCAUUUGCUUUUCCAUUCACUGAUCACAUUAUUCCCCAAUCAAGUUCUUGCUCGAUCCAAAAAAUUAGAUUAGCCCCUUCCUUUCAGUGUCUGUUGUGACAUCACAGAAUUGCCAUAGCAACAGACUGUGAUGUCAACAGACUGCCUGGUGCUGCUAAAAAGAACCACGUUGGUCAAAAAAGGAAUCUGUCAUGUGAAGACAAAAUGGAAUAAUAUAGAAAGCCAGAGGAACUGAAACGUGAUAUCAAAAAGAACAUCUUGGCAGGAUAAGAUAGCAGUGGGUCUGGAGCCUCCUUUGCUAGAACUCUUUACAGAAAACCAAGGAACUUAAUGAGGAUUGAUUGGAGAACAGGCUUGCCUAGAAGCAGGGGGAUGGCAGCGAUGACCUUCGGAAGGCCCUUGCAGUCCAAGGAUCCUAAGACAUGAAGGACAUUAGGAAAGGGGGGAGCGCUGACCAUCUUUAGCCGCUGAAGAAUUCAGGGGAAUUAACAUCGAUACAAACCUCCUUGCUUCUGAGCAGAUCUGACAGUCCCCAGCUGGAAUGUAUCAUCUCGUGUCUGGGAAGAUUUUCAGCCAUAAACACACAGUGACCCCCUCUCAAGCCCCAUUUGCUGCCCUCUUCCUUGCAAGCCUUGAGAGGAAGCUCUCCUUUAAUAUUGCCUGAGCAGCCCCAUCCUAGCCACCAGCUCUGGUUCCACAGCAUCCACGCCCAUCUGGUCGACUUGCUUCUCAUCGGUAGGACUGCCACACAGGGAGGGAAAGCAACCCCGUGCUGUCUGAGGGGAGCAAGUCGGAGGGACAGGGGCAGAGGACCUUCAUUCAUUAUGCUCCUGUCCACACAGAAGAAGGCUGGGCAGGCUGACCGAAGAGAAGGGAGAACUGCUCAAUCAAUCUCAGCUUCUCAGCAGCGGCAGCAAUAACAGCAGAUGAAUCGGGAGCUUCAUUUAACCCUUAUGCCCACAGGAUCUGAAGGAUCUCUGAGAAGCAAGUUGAUUUUCAGCUCAGGAGCCUGUAUUGUGGGUUGAGAAUUGGGGAGGCAGGAGGACUGUCUCCCUACAGGUCGGGCUGGCAUGGGUUUCAGCCGUGCAGAUGGGAAUGCAGCCCCAGACUCCUUCACCCGUCCAGCUACUCUGCGUCCUUAGCUCACUGAGGUCGGACUACCUGGGAGUGCUACACCUGCUCCGUGUAUGCCUGUCUCUCCAUUUCAGCAUUUUCUCCUUGGGGUGCUGAAUGGGGAGGAUAUCAUCCCCUCCUUGUUUAUUCUGCCUCCAGUCCUCUGACCAGUAGCAUUCUGGCCGAAUACCAGGAAGCCACAGGCCUACUAGGGCACCUAGGCGACCCCUACCACCACCCAAGGAGAGUGCCCUCCUGGUUCUCCAGAGCCAGAGCCAGGAGGAGGGAGAACUGCUAGAGACUCUGCCACCAAUCACUCUGCAUCUCUGCCACAGCCUUACGAGUUGGACCAGAGGACUUACUUCUCAGAGGCAUGGUAGGAUCAGGGUGGCCGGCGGGUCCUCUGAGGCUGCCAAACUGGGGACGGAGCUGCCAAAAAGAUGUUGAAGUUUCGGGCUGAUCGACGGGUCAGCCACAAUGAAAGACGGAACACAUUUCUACACCCAGUGACUGGCCAGGUCCCAGAGGAAAACAAAAAAUUUGACUUGAAAAUAUCGACCUUGGACAUGUCCAAUAAAACAGGUGGGAAACGCCCGGCUACCACCAACAGUGACAUACCCAACCACAACAUGGUGUCCGAGGUCCCUCCAGAGCGGCCCAGCGUCCGGGCAACUCGCACAGCCCGCAAAGCCGUCGCCUUUGGCAAGCGCUCACACUCCAUGAAGCGGAACCCCAAUGCACCUGUCACCAAGGCGGGCUGGCUCUUCAAACAGGCCAGCUCCGGGGUUAAGCAGUGGAACAAGCGCUGGUUCGUCCUGGUGGAUCGCUGCCUCUUCUACUAUAAAGAUGAGAAGGAAGAGAGUAUCCUGGGCAGCAUCCCCCUCCUGAGCUUCCGGGUAGCCGCAGUGCAGCCCUCAGACAACAUCAGCCGGAAACACACGUUUAAGGUGACUGUGUGCUGGGUGGAUGAGGCCGAGGCCAGCUCCACACGCUGCCUCUCCCCACAGGCUGAGCAUGCCGGGGUCCGCACCUACUUCUUCAGUGCCGAGAGCCCCGAGGAGCAAGAGGCCUGGAUCCAGGCCAUGGGGGAGGCUGCUCGAGUACAGAUCCCUCCAGCCCAGAAGUCAGUGCCCCAAGCUGUGCGGCACAGCCAUGAGAAGCCAGACUCGGAGAACGUCCCACCCAGCAAGCACCACCAGCAGCCACCCCACAACAGCCUCCCUAAGCCUGAGCCAGAGGCCAAGACUCGAGGGGAGGGUGAUGGCCGAGGCUGUGAGAAGGCAGAGAGAAGGCCUGAGAGGCCAGAAGUCAAGAAAGAGCCUCCGGUGAAAGCCAAUGGCCUCCCAGCUGGACCGGAGCCAGCCUCAGAGCCGGGCAGCCCUUACCCCGAGGGCCCAAGAGUGCCAGGGGGUGGGGAACAGCCUGCCCAGCCCAAUGGCUGGCAGUACCACUCCCCAAGCCGGCCAGGGAGCACAGCUUUCCCGUCUCAGGAUGGAGAGACUGGGGGACACCGGCGGAGUUUCCCACCACGCACCAACCCUGACAAAAUUGCCCAGCGCAAGAGCUCCAUGAACCAGCUUCAGCAGUGGGUGAAUCUGCGCCGGGGGGUACCCCCGCCUGAAGACCUUCGGAGUCCCUCUAGGUUCUAUCCUGUGUCUCGCAGGGUCCCUGAGUACUAUGGCCCCUACUCCUCCCAGUACCCCGAUGAUUAUCAGUACUACCCGCCAGGAGUGCGGCCGGAGAGCAUCUGUUCCAUGCCGGCCUAUGAUCGGAUCAGCCCGCCCUGGGCCCUGGAGGACAAGCGCCAUGCCUUCCGCAAUGGGGGUGGCCCUGCCUACCAGCUGCGAGAGUGGAAGGAGCCCGCCAGCUACGGGCGGCAGGAUGCCACCGUCUGGAUCCCAAGCCCCUCCCGGCAGCCAGUCUAUUAUGAUGAGCUGGAUGCCGCCUCUAGCUCCCUGCGCCGCCUGUCCCUGCAGCCCCGCUCCCACUCUGUGCCCCGCUCACCCAGCCAGGGCUCCUACAGCCGUGCCCGCAUUUACUCCCCUGUCCGCUCACCCAGUGCCCGUUUUGAGCGGCUGCCACCUCGCAGUGAGGACAUCUAUGCUGACCCUGCUGCCUAUGUGAUGAGGCGAUCCAUCAGCUCCCCCAAGGUCCCUCCAUACCCAGAAGUGUUCCGGGACAGCCUCCACACCUACAAGUUAAACGAGCAAGACACAGAUAAGCUGCUGGGAAAAUUGUGUGAGCAGAACAAGGUGGUGAGGGAGCAGGACCGGCUGGUGCAGCAGCUCCGAGCUGAGAAGGAGAGCCUGGAAAGUGCCUUGAUGGGGACCCACCAGGAGCUGGAGAUGUUUGGAAGCCAGCCCGCCUACCCAGAAAAGCUGCGACACAAAAAGGAUUCACUGCAGAACCAGCUCAUCAACAUCCGCGUGGAGCUGUCUCAGGCGACCACGGCCCUGACAAACAGCACCAUAGAGUAUGAGCACCUCGAGUCUGAGGUCUCUGCCCUGCACGAUGACCUCUGGGAGCAGCUCAAUUUGGACACCCAGAAUGAGGUGCUGAACCGGCAAAUCCAAAAGGAGAUCUGGAGGAUCCAGGACGUGAUGGAGGGGCUGAGGAAGAACAACCCCUCCCGGGGCACGGACACCGCCAAGCACAGAGGAGGACUUGGCCCCUCAGCCACCUACAGCUCCAACAGCCCGGCCAGCCCCCUCAGCUCUGCCAGCCUCACCAGCCCCCUGAGCCCCUUUUCACUGGUGUCGGGCUCUCAGGGGUCCCCCACCAAGCCUGGCUCCAACGAGCCCAAGGCAAACUAUGAACAAAGCAAGAAAGACCCCCACCAGACAUUGCCCCUGGACACCCCCAGAGACAUCAGCCUUGUGCCCACCAGGCAAGAGGUAGAGGCAGAGAAGCAGGCAGCUCUCAACAAAGUUGGCGUUGUGCCCCCUCGGACAAAAUCGCCCACUGAUGAUGAGGUGACCCCAUCAGCAGUGGUAAGAAGGAAUGCCAGUGGGCUCACCAAUGGACUCUCCUCCCAGCAGGAACGCCCCAAGAGUGCUGUGUUUCCUGGCGAGGGGAAGGUCAAGAUGAGCGUGGAGGAGCAGAUUGACCGAAUGCGGCGGCACCAGAGUGGCUCCAUGAGGGAGAAGCGGAGGAGCCUGCAGCUCCCGGCCAGCCCGGCCCCCGACCCCAGUCCCCGGCCAGCCUACAAAGUGGUGCGCCGCCACCGCAGCAUCCAUGAGGUAGACAUCUCCAACCUGGAGGCAGCCCUGCGGGCAGAGGAGCCUGGCGGGCAUGCCUACGAGACACCCCGGGAGGAAAUUGCCCGGCUUCGCAAAAUGGAGCUAGAGCCCCAGCAUUAUGACGUGGACAUCAAUAAGGAGCUCUCCACUCCAGACAAAGUCCUCAUCCCUGAACGGUACAUUGACCUGGAGCCUGACACUCCCCUGAGCCCUGAGGAGUUGAAGGAGAAGCAGAAGAAGGUGGAGAGGAUCAAGACACUCAUUGCCAAAUCCAGUAUGCAGAACGUGGUGCCCAUCGGCGAGGGGGACUCUGUGGACGUGCCCCAGGACUCAGAGAGCCAGCUGCAGGAGCAGGAGAAGCGGAUUGAAAUCUCCUGCGCCCUGGCGACCGAGGCCUCCCGCAGGGGCCGCAUGCUGUCUGUGCAAGCCCUGGCUGAGGCCAAUGCUGUGAAGCUCCACAGAGCCACAUUCUGAAGCCGUCCUCUGCCCACCUGAGGUCCUGGCUCCCCACCCUGGCCCCCUGCCCCUGCACUCCCAUGGGAAUGCCGCAGGGAGCCAGGCUGGGGCCAUGGGCUGCUGCCAGAGGACCGUGGAUACCUCAGUGUCCACACACCCACCAUGCCCAGCCCUGGAGCCAUCACUACUCACACCGUGGUCCUGGGCCAGGGCCUGAGAUGACAGUGGGGAGCACCAUCCUCAUUAAUGUCCAAGUCACAGGGAGCCUCAGCCUUGCCCUGGCUGGGGUUGUGGUGACUCCAGUGGAACAUUCCCUGAUGGGGGACAUGCCGUGGUGGAGAACACACCUGUGGCUAUCUUAUGUGAGGACUAGAGGUGAAGAGGAGAUGGACACUGCCUCUGGAGCCAGCCUGACACCAAGGACAGCACUUGUCAUCAUCCCUAUCCUCGUCAGCCCCACCCUACUGCCUCAGCUGGACCCAGGGCUUUGACACAAACCCAGUGCUUUGCUUAUGGGUGCUCGCUGGGGUCCGGUGGAGACUGACCACCCUGCUUGAGCCAAAGACAAGGUGAUGAGAGAUGGGGAGAGGCCAUUGGCUCCCAGAGGGAACAGUGCUGGCUGUGGCUAGAGAACAGCAGGUCUGUGCAGUGUCUGAGGGCAGGUUGGGAAGGGUAGCAGAGAGAGAGAGACAGAAAGAGAGAGAGAGAGAGAGAGAGAGAGAGAUCCUCAGAGUGGAAGGAGGGGGAAGCAGCAGGACACAUUGGCAAGUCAAGCAGGAAGGAGGGAGAUGGAAAGGGGAUAUCAGAUUGGUUUCCCCCGGUGGAGCCUUAGGUUAGUGCCCAGUGCAGUGCCAGACUGUCUCCUCUGCUCCUCCCACCUCAUCCCUAGGAGGACCCACCAGUGGAGCACAUGCAGCCUCAGUGGAGAUGCUUGGUGUGGGGAUCUGGGUGAAGGGGGUUGAGUAGCGACUGCCUGGGAGAUGGCUGUUAGUAGGUCUGUGCCUGGUGUCUGCCUCGCCAUCCUGGGGUAAGGGGCAGAGAGAAGGACUUGUCUUAUGUAGGGUGUGGUCAGCCUUGGGGCCUUACCUACCCAGUUCCAUGAUAUUUCUUGCCCUGUUCCCCCUGGAAUGUGCAGUGGGCCAGCUGAGAGUACGCCUUGAGGAGGGGGGAUGAGGCCUUAAUCUGGGAGGCCUAUCCCCCUAUCCCAGGCAUCCCAGACGAGGACUGGCUGAGGCUAGGCGCUCUCAUGAUCCACCUGCCCCGGGAGGGCAGCGGGGAAGACAGAGAAAAGCAAACGCAUUCCUCCUCAGCUCCACCCACCUGGAGACGAAUGUAGCCAGAGAGGAGGAAGGAGGGAAACUGAAGACACCGUGGCCCCUCGGCCUUCUCUCUGCUAGAGUUGCCGCUCAGAGGCUUCAGCCUGACUUCCAGCGGUCCCAAGAACACCUACUAAUUCCUCUGCACUCCUUCAUGGCUGGGACAGUUACUGGUUCAUAUGCAAGUAAAGAUGACAAUUUACUCAACAAAUAUUUAUCGAGCACCUUUUAUGUACCAGGCACUGUUGUAGGUGCUUAGGAUAUUCUCAUGUUUCUGAGGGAUUACAGCCUGGGAGGAUUCCACCGAUCUUCACUUCUAGCAGGUUUUUUAAACGUGACCCUUGGCUGUAUUUCCCAUCUUCACAGUUCAAGCACCCCAAACCUGCCCUUUCUCCCCUGCAGACUGGCAGGUGGGAUUGGCUCCCAGGUCAUUUCCUCUCUCUCUCUUUCUCCCAAGCCUUUCUCCCUCCACAGGAAACAGAUUUUUCAGGGCCUUCCAUGCCUGCCACUUUGUCCGUCUCUUUUUUUUUUUUUAAAGUAAUAUUUUUUAGAAAUACAUGUAAAAUACCAAGAAAUAAUGUCUGCGCCUCUGCCACCUCUCUCUCAUCUCUUAUUUCAUAAAGCUGGCUCUUUAUGUUGCUUUACAUGCCUUAAUAUAUGUUUUAUGGAGAUUAUACAUAUUAUAGAUCUAUAUAUGUAAUAUAUUUGUUUGGAUGUCUGAUCUUUUCCUACAGUUCCUGCCCAGGCCUGUUUUUCUCUCCCUUAUUUUCCACAUCAUUCCUAGCAUAUCAAGACCAUACCCCUUGCCUUUUUGAUCCAAAGAAGGGGAGAGGAAAGACUUAUUUUAAGACAUCUAUUUUAUGCUUUUGUUUAAAAAAAGCAAAUCUAUUUUCAAAUUGUGCAAUGUCUGAAUGGAAUUGGCAAAUGAGGUGAGGAGAUGGGGUAACUGCCUUUAGGUCCCAACCCUGUGCCUGUCCCUCUGCCACAGUGGCUUCCUUCCAUCCUAUUCCCCAGUCACGAAAGGGCUGGUCCCCAGAGCUCACCCAGAAAGCAUCUUGCCGGGGGCAGGGCAUUCCCUCGGAAGUCCUGGCCUAAGGAUUUUAUUACACUGUCUGCUCCUGAUGACCCUCUGCGGUUGUCAGGCGUGAAUCCUCUGGAAGGAACUGUUUGCAGUUGUAUGCACAAAGGAGACCCAUGCAGGCAUGCACCCCAGAUGGGCUGCUAGACUACCCCUCUUCAUCAGCCUGCUGGAAAGAGCAGACAGCGUAACAGCAGCCUAUGCCAAACAGCACUAAGGAUGUCAGUGUACGAGACGGUGCGAAGCCCAGAGGAGGCGGCUUGGGAUCCUCUGGGCCAUCCCUGGCCCUGUAGCACAGACACAUACAAGUUCCUUGGACUUGUCACACUCCUUUUCACUUGAUCCCUCUCUGGCCUGGGUCACAUUUAUGACAUCCCCCCUCUGCAACCUUUCUCUCUGGGGGCUGUACCAAAGGCAUGGUACCUCAGUCUGGUAUCCAGACUGUGAAAUCAGCCUCUGGGCCAAGGAGGGUCCUACAGACAAGGUGGCAUCUCAACCUCACCCAAGAAACCCCCGGGACUUUACCCCAGCAGGCUGCCACUGGGGCACCGAACUAAGCCAGCUCAGCCUUCCAAGCUGCUUAGCCUUUGUCAACCAUCAAAGUGGGGAAAGGGUCUCUGGCCUUGCAAGGAUUUGGGCAGGAUGGAAGUCUUUGUCUAGGUCUGAAAUCAAGGGCUUGGGAAUCUAGAGCAGAGCUCCUGGCCAGCGUUUGAAGCCUGGCCUCCCACCUGGGGCAUUUACUGACACCCUGUCGCCAGCCUAGAACAUCCUGCUCUGAAUGAACAGAGCCCAGAUGGGGGUCCAGAGCUAAGUGACCCACCUGGGGAAGCUCUGAUUAUUCAUCCAGGGCCUUCUCAAUGAGCACAUUACCUCCAUGAUCAAUAACCAAGAGGCUGCAGUCAAAUACUGCUACUGUCACUUUGAAGAUUUUCUAAGGGCACAAGUGGCACACUUGCUCUCCGGCCUUUGGGAGAGGCAUGUUCUUGGGCAGGGCUGGCUACGGCAAGAGGGAACCAAUUCCUUUCCCCUUUAGGCACCCUCUACCUGGCAGCUCUUAAAACUAAGAAAAAAUAUGAUAUACACACACAUUAUAUAUAUAUAUAUAUAUACACACACACACACACACACACGUAUAUCUAUUUAUGCACAUAUUGGGGCCAAUUUGAUUUGCUAGUAUUAGACAAUAAACUGUACAAGGAAAUUUAUUAUCUCAGUGUCUUUAUUUAGCAUAAAAGUGGCCUUAGAAGAAGGGUGAAGGUUAGAUAGAUGGAAUCUCUGUCAGGGGACAAACAGCUGUAGCAUCCCCUUAGCAUCUUUCUAGCCAAUGAGCCCCCUCCCCAGGAGGAGGGAUGGCCUGACUGAAACAGGUGAGAGUUUGCUUCCCCCUUUCAGCAGCAUUCUUUUUAGAUUUAGGUACUGAAGAAUCCCAGUGAGUUCUGCAUUUGUAUCUUGCAAGUUUGUAUAAACCCAAUACAGGAAAUAAAAUGAAUGGUUUGUA